GCAGCCGGAGUGACGCGUGGCCGCCGGCACCCGGAGCUCCUGGGCACACGGCAUUGGCAGGGGCCGCUUCGGCAGAGUGAUGACUGAUGAUGAGUCCGAGAGCGUCCUCUCCGACUCCCAUGAAGGGUCGGAGCUGGAGCUGCCUGUUAUCCAGCUGUGCGGGCUGGUGGAGGAGCUCAGCUAUGUAAACUCUGCUCUCAAAACUGAGACUGAGAUGUUUGAGAAAUAUUACGCUAAACUGGAGCCCAGGGAUCAGCGACCUCCACGAUUAUCAGAAAUUAAAAUAUCAGCAGCAGAUUAUGCACAGUUUCGAGGCAGGCGUAGAUCCAAAUCCCGGACAGGUAUGGACCGUGGGGUAGGCCUGACUGCCGACCAAAAACUUGAGCUGGUACAAAAAGAGGUUGCGGACAUGAAGGAUGACUUACGACACACAAGGGCAAAUGCGGAACGCGACCUGCAGCAUCACGAGGCGAUCAUUGAGGAGGCUGAAAUUCGAUGGAGUGAAGUUUCGAGAGAAGUGCAUGAGUUUGAAAAAGAUAUUCUAAAAGCCAUAUCCAAGAAGAAAGGGAGUAUUUUGGCCACUCAGAAAGUGAUGAAAUACAUUGAGGACAUGAACCGCCGGAGGGAUAAUAUGAAGGAGAAAUUACGUUUGAAAAAUGUUUCUCUCAAAGUUCAGAGGAAAAAAAUGCUUUUACAAUUGAGGCAGAAGGAAGAGGUGAGUGAGGCCCUUCACGAUGUUGAUUUUCAGCAGUUGAAGAUAGAGAACGCUCAAUUUCUUGAGACAAUUGAAGCAAGGAAUCAAGAACUGACCCAGCUAAAGCUGUCAUCUGGAAACACUCUGCAGGUUCUCAAUGCCUACAAAAGCAAGCUUCACAAGGCAAUGGAAAUAUACCUCAAUCUGGACAAGGAGAUCUUGCUGAGAAAAGAGCUACUUGAAAAAAUUGAAAAAGAAACACUACAAGUAGAGGAGGACCGGGCCAAAGCCGAGGCAGUGAAUAAGAGGCUCCGGAAGCAGCUGGCCGAGUUCCGGGCACCACAGGUGAUGACUUACGUCCGGGAGAAGAUCUUAAAUGCGGACCUGGAGAAGAGCAUCAGGAUGUGGGAAAGGAAAGUGGAGAUAGCAGAGAUGUCCUUAAAAGGCCAUCGUAAGGCUUGGAAUCGAAUGAAAAUAACCAAUGAGCAGUUGCAGGCAGAUUACCUUGCUGGGAAGUAGCCAGAGGCAGGCCACGGCUUACAGACCACUACAUGACCUAUAAAAGUAAUCAGCUCCUUUCUAGUCACGGGCUCCUCUCACUGUUCCCUGUCUGCCUGGUGUUCCCAACCCCCCACCCAGGCUGCGUAUCAUCUCCUGGGCCACAUCUGCCCAUGGGGAGUGUUUUCACAGCCUGGCCCCUGGAACUGUUACCACUGAAAGAACCACAGGGCACUCUAAUGGUUUGACACUUGUUAGCCAGCAUUUAGUUCACAAGCAUAGUGAAAGUGACCUUCCCACACCUGGGAGAGGGAUAGAGGAGGGAGAGCCAGCCCAGUGUAUGCCAUGGGCUUAUCCGUGGCAGCCCCAGUGUGCAACUAUCAAAAACAGACAUCAAAACAGCAUGGUGAAUGCCUGGCACUCAGCAUUCUCAGUUUACUCUUCAGUUUGGUGGGGUAGCUCCUGGACUAGAUACUGCUGCAAAAGAAAACAAGCACGAAGGAAACCAAGAUGAUUUCUUCGGGCUGAUACAACCUGUUCUGACCUGCAAAAAUCCUACCUUCCCCCACCUCCCCACCGUAAUAGUCAUAGUAUAAGGGUUGUACAGACGCCUCAGGAGACCUGCCUGAUUCCUUUACAUCCUUCUCCCUAACAUCUAGACUAUCUCUAGAGCUGUUUCCUAGUCGUGAAUGCGUGAUGGUCCUUCUUUGUCCCUGCAAGUAUGAUCCAACAUGGCCCAGUUCAGAAUCAGAAUAUGUCUUCUGUGUCAUGGUGGCAUUUGGUCCAUGGUGGGAGAAAGAAAUCAACUUUUCCCAGUGGUGGAGUGAGGACAGGGGAGGGCCGGCCCUCUCAGCCUUGGAUGUGAUCCAUUUGCUGUAGUCUUCCACCUUGGUGUACAGAAACAGGCCAGGGCACGUCUCACCACCGAAGUUCAGGACUCCUCUCAGAACCCACAGAUCGAACUGCUGUAGCUGGCACAUCAUUGGGCUUCCUGGGUCCCCCUGUGAUAAAAGACAGAAGGCUUCAAGUCUUAGAAAAACUAGUUUUUGUUGUAAAUCUAUCCUUGUGCAAUAUACUGUUUGUUCUAGAAAUGUUUUACGCUGGUUCUCACUGGAAAUGGGGCAAAUUAUAGGAUACAAUUUCAAAUCUAGGCAGCCACCACCACAAAUUCCAACAAGAUGACUUUUCCUUUUAUUAUGCAAAUUAGCUGUGGACUUCUGCUGAUUGCCUAUAGCUUCCUGGUUCAUAUUUCAUUUUCUUGCCCCUUUCCAGUCCUUUGGCCAAACCUUCCCUCUCUUCUGGCUUCUCAUUCCUGAAAUGUUGGUGUUUGUUUCUGUUUUGUCCUGAAAUGCUCACAUUUUCCCUUCUCUGCCUUGCUUCAACCCUUAGUGUAAGCCACUUCCUGCCACCUGGCAACUGCUUACCAGCCUGGCUGGCCGUGCUCUGGGUCUUCCCUACUCCCAAUGGAGCAGUCCUCUGGGACUUGGGAAUUCUGCCACAUACACUUUAUCUAACUUAAAGUGACGGAGUAGAAGCUUGGCAUCAUUAGCUAGAUAUGGGACCCUGGCAAGUGACCAAAUCCUCUCUGAGCCAAGGUGGGAACACAGUUAAUGCCUGUAACACGUGCUGAGCACAGCACAGUGCCUGGCACACAGCAAACACUCAAUAGAAUAUUAGCUACCAUCAUCCUGAUGUCGCUAUAAAGGCCAGCAUUUUUCUGAAAAGUUGGGGAAAAUGGGAAAAGCAACAAGGCAACUAGUAGGUAUCACUUACCUUACCUGCCCAGACCCCACACCCCUAGGUCUCCUCUCAAAGGAAUUCCUGCCCCUCCCAUGGCCCAUCUUGGUCCGAGAAGGGGGUGGUCAUCCCCAGGCUAGCCAGCCACUUCUGACCUGUGUGGCCUGCCUGGCUGGAAGGCCCAGGCAAUGACAUGUUGCUCUCGCAGUUUGGACUGAGACAUGGAAUGGGGCCGCAAUUAACAACAGGAAACAAUCUGAACAGACUGAACCACGAGCAGCAGAAAGGCAGAAGAGCAGCCGCUUCAGCCCCUUACCAUCCGAGACCUGGGUGUGUGGUCUGUCUUGGUCACUCUCUCUGUCUCUCUUUCUCUCUUUCUUUCUCUGUCCCCAAGGCUGGAGUGCAGUGGUGCAAUCUUGGCUCACUGCAACCUCCACCUCUGGGAUUCAAGCAAUUCUCCCACCUCAGCCUCUCGAGUAGCUGGGGCUACAGCUAUGCGCCACCAUGCCCAGCUAAUUUUUUUUUUUUUUUUUGAGAUGGAGUCUUGCUCUGUCCCCCAUGCUGGAGUGCAGUGGCAUGAUCUCGGCUCGCUGCAACCUCCUCCUCCUGGGUUCAAGCGAUUCUCCUACCUCAGCCUCCCCAGUAGCUGGGAUUACAGGCGCCCACCACCACACCUGGCUAAUUUUUAUUUUUAGUAGAGAUGGGGUUUCACCAUGUUGGCCAGGCUGGUCUCGAACUCCUGACCUCAUGAUCCACCCGCCUCGGCCUCCCCAAGUGUUGGGAUUACAGGCGUGAGCCACUGCACCCGGCCUAAUUUCUGUAUUUUUAGUAGAGAUGGGGUUUCACGAUGUUGGCCAGGCUGGUCUUAAUCUAACUUCAAGUGAUCUGCCCGCCUCGCCCUCUCAAAGUGCUGGGAUUAGGCAUGAACUACCAUGCCCAGUGGGGUAUUCUCUUUCAAUAAAGCUCCUCUUUUCCAAGGAAGCCACACCAGAACAGAGAUGAAGACCAGUGGGAAAACAUGGGAGCAACUCCGUGGGCAGGCCAGCGGGGAGGCCAUGCUGCAAAGCUGCCGUGAUUCCCUGGUGAUCUCUCAGCAGGCCAAGGCCAGACAUGUGAGGAAGGCCUUGAGGACUUCAUUCUGUGCCUCUCCUUGGAUGGAAGGGGGUGCUUUAGUGUGGCACUCCUGACUUUUCAAUUGACUGGUGAAGAGGCCCUUGUGUGCACCUCACUAUGUCUGCCUAGGUCAUGGGGGCUCCCUGGCCAAGAAUGACGUGGUUCCCCCUUUCAUCAGUCCGAUUCGCAGUUUGUCUUAACUGUAGUGGUAUAGCCAGAGCAAGAAAAAGAAUGUGAUUUAGGACAAAUGAUUGGAUGAGUGAUUGGUAGAUGUCCUCAGCUAUGGCGUGGUUUUGCAGGUCACUGUUCCACCCACCUGGGCACAGCAUAUACGCUUUUUCUCUUCCCCAUAAUCCUGUAGGGGCUGCGACUUCUGAAGCACAAGAGGCAGAGGCGAACAGCUCCAGGUGCCCCUCUGGAGCUACCCUACCUCAUCUCCCAAGGGAGCGGCCACAGCCCAGAGUGGGGUCUUUCAUUUUGUGAUCUUUUCCCUUGACAUUCAGCAAAAGCCCUGACAGUGGUAGAAUAAAGGCAGGAUGGGUGAGUGCAGAGUGAUUCUGCUUUUGUUGGGUUUCAGGGAAACCCAUAGGCAGAUUCUGAACCUGGUGGUUGAUUCUACAUGUGGGAAUUGUGGCUUUGAAGACCUCUGGACAUGAGAACAUAUUUCCAAGACAGAGGAUUCUAUGGGGACGGGUCACCAUUAAAUGGUGUGCAAGCAUAAUUCUGUUCAAAAAUGAAGGCAUGUUUAGAGGUGUGUCACAGUUAAAAACCAACCUGAACUUUGCAGUUAGAUUUUAAAAGAUGGUCAGUUAGAGUAGAAAUAGCUUAGAAUAUUCCAUUGAGUCUAAGAUACAGUUAGAAAUCAACAUCUUUGAAAUUAGGGUGUGUCUUUUAAUCAGUUGAUGUCAGAGUUUAACGGGCAGCAUUUUUUUCUUUCUUGGGAUUACAAAAAAUGAUGGUGCAUUCUAUAAUUGGCAGCAUCUUAGAUCUGAGGAAGUAUGAUACUUGUUUGACGGAAUGGUUGACGGCAGAAUUUUGUUAAAAAGCUAUAUCUUCACUGUAUUUUAACACAUUAUCUAAUUUAAGAAAUUGUUAAGAUCCCCCACCUGGCAGAGGACCCAGUACAAAAUAGGCACUCAAUAGAUGUUACACCAACUUUGGAAGGGCAAACAUAUUUCUUAAUGAGAGGCAGUCCUUCAUGUUUUGCAAUAAAAUGACUUUUAAAAAAAA